AGGGUCCGCGAUCUCGGACUAAGGAUGCGGUCCCGGGUUCUGUGGGGCGCUGCCCGGUGGCUCUGGCCCCGCCGGGCCGUUGGCCCAGCCCGCCGGCCCCUGAGCUCCGGUAGCCCGCCGCUGGAGGAGCUGUUCACCCGGGGCGGGCCCUUGCGGACCUUCCUCGAGCGCCAGGCGGGGUCUGAAGCCCAUUUGAAGGUCAGGAGGCCCGAGUUGCUGGCGGUGAUCAAACUGCUGAACGAGAAGGAGCGGGAGCUGCGGGAGACUGAGCACUUGCUGCACGAUGAGAAUGAAGAUUUAAGGAAACUUGCAGAGAAUGAAAUCACUUUGUGUCAAAAAGAAAUAACUCAGCUGAAGCAUCAGAUUAUCUUACUUUUGGUUCCCUCAGAAGAAACAGAUGAAAAUGAUUUGAUCCUGGAAGUAACUGCAGGAGUUGGAGGUCAGGAGGCAAUGUUGUUUACAUCAGAGAUAUUUGAUAUGUAUCAGCAAUAUGCUGCAUUUAAAAGAUGGCAUUUUGAAACCCUGGAAUAUUUUCCAAGUGAACUAGGUGGCCUUAGACAUGCAUCUGCCAGCAUUGGGGGUUCAGAAGCCUAUAGGCACAUGAAAUUUGAAGGAGGUGUUCACAGAGUACAAAGAGUGCCAAAGACAGAAAAGCAAGGCCGCGUCCAUACUAGCACCAUGACUGUAGCAAUAUUACCCCAGCCUACUGAGAUUAAUCUGGUGAUUAAUCCGAAAGAUUUGAGAAUUGACACUAAGCGAGCCAGUGGAGCUGGGGGGCAGCAUGUAAAUACCACGGACAGUGCUGUCCGGAUAGUUCAUCUUCCAACAGGUGUUGUUUCUGAAUGUCAACAAGAGAGAUCUCAGCUGAAAAAUAAAGAGCUGGCUAUGACAAAGUUACGUGCAAAACUGUACAGCAUGCAUCUAGAAGAAGAAAUAAAUAAAAGACAGAAUGCUAGAAAAAUUCAGAUUGGAAGUAAAGGAAGAUCAGAGAAAAUAAGAACAUAUAAUUUUCCACAGAACCGGGUCACAGAUCACAGAAUAAACAAGACGCUGCAUGAUCUUGAAACUUUUAUGCAAGGAGAUUAUCUACUGGAUGAACUUGUACAGUCAUUGAAGGAAUACGCCGAUUAUGAAUCUUUAGUAGAAAUUAUUUCCCAAAAAGUUUAAGUUGAUUUGUUAUUUAUAGACUUUCGUAGCUUAGAAAAAUUCUACAGUACAUCCACAUAGGGUGAAAGUACCCUUACUCUCUUGAAAAACGUUGAGUUAACACAGUUGGAGGUAAUAUGCAUAUUCUGAAGUCAUAGAUAAUUUACACAGAUCUCUCUCAAUGCAUUAGCAAAAAUCAUACAAUAUACAGAUGGUCCUCGAUUUACAUUGUGGUUAAUUCCCAAUAAACCCAUCAUAAGUUAAAAAUGCAUAUAACGUUAGCAACACAGCAGUCUCCUAAUUAAUGACAGCUUGACUUAACAAUUUUCCAACUUUACCAUGGUGUGAAAGAGGUAUGAUUCCUAAGCCCUAAGGAGCUCCUCAGCUUGAAAUGGGGCUGCAUCCCUAUAAACCCAUCAUAAAGUCAAAAAAUCCUAAAACAUAAGUUGGUGACCAUCUGUAAUCAUGAUGUGGUGGUAAAUCUUGGACGCUACCUUACAAUAACUAGACAAAGGAAAAUCAUCCUUUGUCCUGUUCUGUGUAAAUAUUUAAUGAAUGAUCAAAACUUCAGUUUAAAUAUUAUGAAAAACUUUAAACAUAAAGUAGUAGAAAUAAGACAGUAAAUACUGUAUCCUAAUAUCCAGUCAGGAUACAGAAACCAUACCAUUAACUUGAACAGGGAUAAUUUUAAUAUAAAAACUGUUAACUGAUAAUGGUAUUAACUUUUAAGAGGGAUGAAAGAGAGCUAUGAUGUCCUAGGACUGAGAGUACCCCAGGAAAGAAUACCCUUGAAAGGGUCUCCCCUUCCCCAUGGUGAAGUCAGGCCUAAUGGAGAGAGUGGCUACAGCCUACUCAGUGAUUGGGAAAUUCCCUGUCUUGCCCUGGGCCAGAGCUGGUGUACCGCUGGUGGAUCAGGUCUUACAAGCAAAGAACCUCACACUCCCAACUGGUAAGCCAGAAGCCUCUUGCUAGGGUGUGAGCAAAACUUGGACAGGAACUCUCAGUAGAUGUUUGUGUUUGUCAAGAUUCUCCAGACAAACUUCCUUAAAAGGAUUGGCUUGUGUUGUUAUUAUUAAGUCUAACAAGUCCAAAAGCUGGAGUGUGAGGCAGGAGGCUGGAAACCCAGGAAAGCUGAUGGUGCAAGGUCCAGUCCAAAGGUAUCUGUUGGAGGAUUCUCUUGUUCUGGGAAGAGGACGGUCUUUUUUUCUCUUCAGACCUUCACCUGACUGGAUCAAGCCCACUAACAUCGAGGAGGACAGUCUGCAUUACUCAGAGUUCACUGAUUGAUUUAAAUGUCAAUCUCAUAUAAAACACCCUCACAGAAACACCUAGAAUAAUGUUUGACCUUAUAAUUGGAAAAUCAGAGCAAAAGUUAAAUCUCAAAAAAAAAAAAAAAAAAAGUAUGACCCAGUAGCUAGGCACCUGUGGCCCCGCCAAGUUGACACAUAAAAUUAACUGUCACAGUAUCAUCUUAGAAGUGAAAGAAGCCCCUUUAUCCUGCAGUGCCCCUCUACCACCACCUACUGACAAAGAACAUGGUGCUAUCUGGCAUGGGAGAAAUGUUCAGUUUGCUAUGGCUUGUAUGUGUCCCCUCAAAUUCAAGUGUUGCCAAUGUGACAGCAUCAAGAGGUGGGGUCUUUAAGAGAUCACUAGGCCAUGAGGGAUUCUCUUAGGACUGGGAUGAAGGCCCAUAAUAAAAGAGGUUUCGGGGAGCAUCCUGCUAGCUUGCCUUCUGUAUGUGAGAACACAGCAAGAAAGCCCUAGUCAACAAGUGCCAGCUCCUUGAUCUUAGACUUCCCAUCCUCCAGAACUGUGAGAAAUACAUUUCUGUUCCUUACAAAUUACCCAGUCUCCUGUAUUCUGUUAUAGCAGCACAAAAUGAAGAUACCAUACCUGAACACCUGAACAUUCUUCACAAGGUAGUAAAUGCACUGCUUUAUUCUGGUCUCAGUAUUGUGUGCUUAAUAAGGAAAUGAGAAAGGGUGGAUCAGGGCAUAGGAUGAACAAGUUACUGCUAGACCUCUCACAAUGCCACUAAUGGAUAAGAUUGUAUUUUCAUCAUUCUUGUCUCUUCGGAAGCUAACACCAUGCUAUAAUAGGCACUAAAUAGAUGUCUAAAAACACCUUAAGUAUUUGUCUAGAAAUCUGGUGCAUUGUUCAGAAAGAACCAAAAUUCAAAAUAAUUUCAAAGGGCCUAAAGCACUAGUUAAUCAAAAUUCAUUAGUUUUUAAUGGUACUACCACUCUCAAAUUUAAAAUGUCAUCUUACGUUCCUCUUCCUCGCAUUGGAUUUAUUGCUAAAACCUGGUAAACACUUUUAAUCCUUUUCAAUUCCAUUACCACUGCUCUUGUCCAGAAUUACUUCGCAGACUAAUAGUCACCUGACUUCUCCCCUGCAUCCGAUUUGCUGUCUAAUUCUGGUUACAAAUAAGUAACUGCCAAACUAAUCUUUCUAAAAAGCAAGACUGAUCUCGUCACUCCUUUGCUCAACAAUGUAAAAGCUCCCAUUGUCUCCCAAAUAAAACCAGCUUUCCACUGUGUAUACAAUACAUCCA